AAGCAGGACUACUUCCGCCGACAAGGAGGCAGCCAAUGUAGAAAAUGCUGGAAUUUUUCCUUGGAACUGGACUGUGAUGAGAGCUUGCGCUAAAUGAAUUCAUCAAGUGACUGAAGACAACCAGUGAUGGACGGGGUGAAUGAUAGCUCCUUGCAGGGCUUUGUUCUGAUGGGCAUAUCAGACCAUCCCCAGCUGGAGAUGAUCUUUUUUAUAGCCAUCCUCUUCUCCUAUUUGCUGACCCUACUUGGGAACUCAACCAUCAUCUUGCUUUCCCGCCUGGAGGCCCGGCUCCAUACACCCAUGUACUUCUUCCUCAGCAACCUCUCCUCCUUGGACCUUGCUUUCGCUACUAGUUCAGUCCCCCAAAUGCUGAUCAAUUUAUGGGGACCAGGCAAGACCAUCAGCUAUGGUGGCUGCAUAACCCAGCUCUAUGUCUUCCUUUGGCUGGGGGCCACCGAGUGCAUCCUGCUGGUGGUGAUGGCAUUUGACCGCUACGUGGCAGUGUGCCGGCCCCUCCGCUACACCGCCAUCAUGAACCCCCAGCUCUGCUGGCUGCUGGCUGUGAUUGCCUGCCUGGGUGGCUUGGGCAACUCUGUGAUCCAGUCAACAUUCACUCUGCAGCUCCCAUUGUGUGGGCACCGGAGGGUGGAGGGAUUCCUCUGCGAGGUGCCUGCCAUGAUCAAACUGGCCUGUGGCGACACAAGUCUCAACCAGGCUGUGCUCAAUGGUGUCUGCACCUUCUUCACUGCAGUCCCACUAAGCAUCAUCGUGAUCUCCUACUGCCUCAUUGCUCAGGCAGUGCUGAAAAUCCGCUCUGCAGAGGGGAGGCGAAAGGCGUUCAAUACGUGCCUCUCCCAUCUGCUGGUGGUGUUCCUCUUCUAUGGCUCAGCCAGCUAUGGGUAUCUGCUUCCGGCCAAGAACAGCAAACAGGACCAGGGCAAGUUCAUUUCCCUGUUCUACUCGUUGGUCACACCCAUGGUGAAUCCCCUCAUCUACACGCUGCGGAACAUGGAAGUGAAGGGCGCACUGAGGAGGUUGCUGGGGAAAGGAAGAGAAGUUGGCUGAGAGAACACUCCUUCGUUAUUUAUUGCGUCUUCAUCUCUACAUGCGUUUCUCAUUAACUCUCUCUGGCCAGGUGAACAUGAGGAAUACUAAUUCCGGUAAAACCAAGGCAUGUUCCUGACAGCCCUAAGCUGACAGCCCUAAGCUGUUGGGAACAUGGUUAGUGUUAUUCGUAAUGUUCUACACUUAUUUACCAAAAAUCCUACUGUGGACUACCGAUAGCAGGGGAGACAUGUUGUUGAGGGCUCAGAGGUUAUUGACCUGUGACAGACCUGUCUCACUGUCUCUGUCUCUGUUGCCCACAUGUUAUUUAAUAUGCCUUAUAUUUCUGCAGAAUUCUGUACUUUUCUAAGCAAAGCACCUCCACUUGCAGUAUCUUACAUAAUGUUACUAUAAUUCCAUAAAAUCAAGCCAUGUAUUAUUAACUUCAUAUGAAGACCCAAACAAUUCAUGUUUUUACCCUAUCUGUCAUUAUCUUUGCCUACCUCUUUUUGUCUCUUCUUCAUUUUUUUUAAGAGUUGGAGUCUUGCUCUGUUGCCCAGGCUGAAGUAGAGUGGCAUGAUCUUAGCUCACUGCAGCCUUCAACUCCUGGGCUCAAGCAAUCCUUCAGUCUUCUGAGUAGCUGGGACUAUAGGCACAUGCUACCACACCUAACUAAUUUUUAUUUUUAUUUUUUACAGAUGGGGUCUCACUCUGUUAACAGCCCAGGCUGGUCUAGAAUUCUUGGCCUCAAGUAAUCUUCCUGCCUUGACUUCCCCAAGUGCUGGGAUUAUGGGUGUGAUCUACCGCACCUGGCCUGUCUCUUCUUAAUAAUGCAGUAUACCACUGGGUGCAGUGGCUCACACCUGUAAUCCCAGCACUUUGGGAGGCCGAGGCGGGUGGAUCACCUGAGGUCAGGAGUUCGGGACCAGCCUGACCAACAUGGAGAAACACUGUCUCCACUAAAAAUACAAAAUUAGCCUUGCAUCGUGGCACAUGCCUGUAAUCCCAGCUACUCGGGAGGCUGAGGCAGGAGAAUCGCUUGAACUCGGGAGGCAGAGGUUGUGGUGAGCUGAGAUCGUGCCAUUGCACUCCAGCCUGGGUAACGAGCAAAACUCCGUCUCAAUAAUAAUAAUAAUAACAAUAAUAAUAAUGUAGUAUAUCUGUCCAUACUUUCCAUCCAUAUAUCUCUCCAUCAUCUUGUUUACCCUCUCCCUUAUGCCUAUAUUCCAAUUUCUCUUCUACUAAUCUAUUAUUUAAUAAUAAAAGAUUAAGCCAGGCA